AGAGCGAGCGGCGCCGGCGUCAUGUGACUGCCCGGAGUUGGUGCCAGGAGCCAGAGGGGAGCCAGGAGCGGAGCCGCGCGGAGCCGGGGCCCGAGCCGGAGCGCAGCGAGAGCGCCCGCCGCACGCGCGCCCGUCCCCGUCCCCUGCGGCCGCCAACGCCGCCCGGACUGGAGCCCUGACAUUGCUGCGCUCGGGGGGCUCCAGGCAGCCCGUAUCGGGGCCUUUAUUUCUCGUCGGCGGCGCCCUGCACCGCGCCUCGCAAAGCCAAACACCAGAGCACCCUAGAAGGUUUAACUAAAAGAAUGCUCAUGUUUGACCCAGUUCCUGUCAAGCAAGAGGCCAUGGACCCUGUCUCAGUGUCAUACCCAUCUAAUUACAUGGAAUCCAUGAAGCCUAACAAGUAUGGGGUCAUCUACUCCACACCAUUGCCUGAGAAGUUCUUUCAGACCCCAGAAGGUCUGUCGCACGGAAUACAGAUGGAGCCAGUGGACCUCACGGUGAACAAGCGGAGUUCACCCCCUUCGGCUGGGAAUUCGCCCUCCUCUCUGAAGUUCCCGUCCUCACACCGGAGAGCCUCGCCUGGGUUGAGCAUGCCUUCUUCCAGCCCACCGAUAAAAAAAUACUCACCCCCUUCUCCAGGCGUGCAGCCCUUCGGCGUGCCGCUGUCCAUGCCACCAGUGAUGGCAGCUGCCCUCUCGCGGCAUGGAAUACGGAGCCCGGGGAUCCUGCCCGUCAUCCAGCCGGUGGUGGUGCAGCCCGUCCCCUUUAUGUACACAAGUCACCUCCAGCAGCCUCUCAUGGUCUCCUUAUCGGAGGAGAUGGAAAAUUCCAGUAGUAGCAUGCAAGUACCUGUAAUUGAAUCAUAUGAGAAGCCUAUAUCACAGAAAAAAAUUAAAAUAGAACCUGGGAUCGAACCACAGAGGACAGAUUAUUAUCCUGAAGAAAUGUCACCCCCCUUAAUGAACUCAGUGUCCCCCCCGCAAGCAUUGUUGCAAGAGAAUCACCCUUCGGUCAUCGUGCAGCCUGGGAAGAGACCUUUACCUGUGGAAUCCCCGGAUACUCAAAGGAAGCGGAGGAUACACAGAUGUGAUUAUGAUGGAUGCAACAAAGUGUACACUAAAAGCUCCCACUUGAAAGCACACAGAAGAACACACACAGGAGAAAAACCCUACAAAUGUACAUGGGAAGGGUGCACAUGGAAGUUUGCUCGGUCUGAUGAACUAACAAGACAUUUCCGAAAACAUACUGGAAUCAAACCUUUCCAGUGCCCGGACUGUGACCGCAGCUUCUCCCGUUCUGACCAUCUUGCCCUCCAUAGGAAACGCCACAUGCUAGUCUGAUUGCCUCUGUGUCCUGCCUCAGCGUGACUCCCCACUCACCUGGCUCUCUCUCUGUCCUGCCUCCCAUUAUCUAACACAUUUUUUACAUGUACAUUUUAAUUUGAUUCAGCUGGUCUGAAUCUCUGAAUUUAUAUCAUCCAAAACUUCCAUAUGGUCAGUAGUAGAUGUUCUCUAAUCCUCCCUCUCCUUACCACGGGUCAGACCUAAAGAAUGUGAACACUUUUUUUUUUUUUUCUGGGGAUGCUAAGCAAACCCUUCUUACAGAUACGUUUAAUGUAAUAAGAACAAGGGAACAUGUAAACUAACAUAACCAAUUGUCAGUUCUCCAUGUAUUCCUCAAAAGAAUGUCAGAGUAAAUGUAUUAGAAAUACAGUAUCCAGACUGCUAGUCCUUGCCAGAGACAUUCUUACCUCUGCCCUGUGAUAAUAUUUUAUGCUUGACAGUGAAAACAAGUGUGGCCCCUUGCACCGGUUAGCUAGAAGUACAGCCAGAUUUCAAGCUAGUGCAGUCACCUCUUCCGUCAUUCUUCACAAAUCUUGUCAACCUGGAUCUUAGACUUCAUCUGAAUCGAGUUCUUUGCCCUCCUUUGUGCCUGCAGCUCAUAUGGAGGUCUUUGCCACCAAUGGGAGAUGAGCCCAAACUUUCGAUCUAGGUGGGUGAUGUGUAGCAGUUCAAGGGAAGGGUGCUGUGUUUUCAUAGCAUGGAGUCGGAGGAGAGGGCCAUUUAGCAGGGGGAGCAGAAGAGGCAAUUCCUCCUGGGCUAGGGGUUGUCAGUGAGGUUUCAACAUUUUGUUAGCUGUGUGCAGCAUUCCCAGAGCUUCAGUCUCUGUGCAUACUCAGCUUUGUAGAACCAUGCUGCAAAGCCAUAUACCGAUGGGGUUAUCCAUGCAACUAUCUCCAUUCCUACAAUGUCCUUAAUAUGAGAUCAUCAAACAUUGAUAGUAGGGACUCCAUGGAAUAUUUGCCCAGUAAUGGUAAGAAAUCUUUCGGGUAAGAGUAUGGAUGGUUCUUCUUUUACCCAAUCUGCUUAUAGCUUUUUUUGUAAACAGGGAAAUGUUGAGUGGUACUUGUAUUCCCUUAUCAAAUUAAUCACAUAGCUUUUAUACAGAAACUCUUCCUGUGUGAGCUGUUAAGGUGCCAAAUUGGCUGUCAUUUGUAUUCAUGACACAUACCAUAAAGCAUCUGCUAAUGCUUUAAUGGAUUGAUUCAAUUAAGACCUGAGUGACACUAUUUGUAAAUAUAACUAGUUGUGAAGCACACAUACCUUUAUUUUGGGAAUUUAUGAGAAAAUAUAGAAAACCACAGAUCAGGGAUUCAUAUAUGUAGCUCAAAAAUUCCCAAAAGUUUACUGUUAGAGUUGGCAAUUUCCUAUCACUAUUUCAGUGUCAGAACAAACUGAAAAUAAUGGCUCGUGUUUAUGUUGAAGAUAAAUAGCACCAUUAUUGGGGGAAGUUAUUCAAAAGCAGGCUUUUGAGCACCAUAGUCUAAAUGCCAAUAAAAAUAAUUCAUACAUAGAAAUGUCAUUGGUCCUGAAUUUGAAGAAAGUGAGCAACAGUAGUUAAAUGUGGGUGCAUAUAACCAAAUUCCCCUUCAUCAAGAAUGGAGGAGAAGAGAGAAGAAUGAAAUCCUGAAGAUUCAUCCCAGCCGCAACUCAGGAUCCAACACAACUUUAACUGGGAGGAAUACAUUGUUUGAUCAUUUUUAAAACAUCUGUGAAUGAGUGAUUCCGGAGGCCUGUGAAUUGUGUGGGGAGCUUGCUUUGAUGGCACUGUGUUAAUAAAAGUUGUAGGGACUGUGCACCUAAGAGGCUAAGAGGUCCCACUCAUCCGCCCUGUGAACCAGCUGUAAAGAAAUGUAGUUAAGAAAUGCAAAGAAAUGUGUUAUCUUGGCACUUGGGUUUGAUUUUCCUUUUUUUAAAGCACUGCAAAACUUCUUUAGGAUACUAAAACAUCCUAAUUGGGCUGUUUUUUUGUUUUGUUUUGUUUUUCAGCUAAAGGCAAAGAUAAUUUUUUUUUCAGCUGAAGUUUUUCUUUUUUGCAACUAUGACAUGAAUUGAGUGAUAAAAUGGCUCUUUGAAAAGUAGAUAUUGUCUGUAUUGUAAAUGCUUAGUCAUAUUCAUGGCAAAGUGUUCAUUUCUUGAGAUGGUUCUUUCACAACACACAAGAAUCAAGAUGGAACGCAAGGAAAAUCUUUUUGUUUUGACCGAGGUAACCAGUUUAUGUGUGUUCCAAUCCAUAGAGAAGUGGGGGAAAGGGCGAGAAAGGAUCAGAUUGAUCUGGGAUCAGCUUUGAGCCUGAGUUCAGUGAAUAGCCUCAUGGGCAUCUCAUGGAAUUGAUGCAUUUGCUGUGGCAUAUUUAAAUUUUGUUCAAAAGAUUUGAAGCAAGACCUUGCAAAGACUCUUAACAUUACUGUUCAGCUUGCUUAGAUUGUGUUAACAGUUCAUUUAACAAAGAUCCGUUUUAACUCUGAACAAAAGCAACCCAGAGCGGCCAUUCUCUAUUCCCAUGCUGGUCAAUACGCUUUCAUUACCAAUUGGCCCUUACCAAACUUUUCUUAUAUAUAUAUUUGUAUUUUACUAUGAUAGUUGAGAAAUUUAGCCUCUUAGUCAUUUUUAGCUGUUAUUGUGGAAGACCUCAAAUACAAGAUUAGAUGCCCUUGAACAUGUUUUAAUGAUGUGUGUCAUGUUACUAUCAAUGGUGAUUUCAAUCGCAAUAUUUUAAAUUGAUGAGAAUGAUUUGUAAACAUGAAGUUACUAUUACGUAAAUUCUGUUUGUUAUAGAGUUUCUUCAGUUGUUACCCAAGUGUCAUCCUAGAGAAGUCAGAAGAAUCAGAAUCCAUCGUAUUUUAGAGUUAUGUGAAUCUACAUCAUAAAUGGGCAUUAACAUUCUAAAUUGCUUGGUUUGGAGAAUGUGUUAGCAGCAUAGCUAUAUUCAACUAGGGAGAUGCUAAAUACACAGAAGUUUCAAGAGCCUUGGAACAGAAUUACAGGGGAACUAUAUAUGUAUAUGUAUAUUUUAUUAAACACCCAUCUGCACUAUCAGUAUUGCACUAAUGUGGAAUUUGAAAGACUAUUUUGCUGAUACUGUAUAUAUGCGCAUCAUUCCUGAUUAGAUUGUUGUAAAGACAAUCUGAAAGAUCUAAGGUUUUAAAAUAAUUUGGUUUGAAAAUAUACAGUUGUCUUGAAGGAAUUGCUGUCAUACAUGAAGUUGCUCCGAGCUGUCUUUAUUCUCUUCUUGGUCAAGGUUAACAAUUGCUAAAUGAUCGCAAAUUCACCUAAACAAUACAUUUACAAAGCCAUCUUUACAUGCAUUAAACGAGGGCUACAACAAUAUUGUUUUACAAAUACUAGCACUUUUUUUUCUGUUAUGUACUUAGUGUUAGAGGGUCAAAAUAAUCUUUCUGCUUAGCAUCUCUUAAACCAUACCUGCAAAUAUAGCAGGAUUAUUACAUUUACAGUACUUUAAUACUUGUAUAAACUAUGCAGAAAUUUUUAAUAAAGUGUAAUAUAUUUUAUAAGCUAAUAAGACUGAAUGGGUAAAGGUUUUUAGCAUGCAUUAGUAUACUUGCAGAUACUGAAACAUUUUGGUAAUCUUUCUUACUAAAGAUGUGAAUGUUUAAUGUACCUUCUCUGUUUCUACUCUGUAGUCCAAUGGGAAUUCAGUAAUGACAUUUUGUCAUGUCAAACUGUGAACAUAAAUUUGUACUGUACAGUCCUCAUAUACUAUAUACAGUAUGCAAUAUAUAUUAUAUACUUGUUAAUAAAACCAUCAGAAUAUUAAAUGUGAUCAUGUGAUUACUUCAUAUGCAGUGAUCACUAGAGCAAAACUUACAGAGCAAUGUAAGAACCCUUGCUUAGAACAUUACUUACUCUGAUGGGCAGUUAUUGUUGAUGGAGGGACAGAAAAAUAGAUCUAACUGGAAGAUGAACUACCGGAAUUAACUCAGCCCUCAAGCUAUGUCCCUGGUUUUCUGAAAACAGCCAACAGGAAGUCUCCUAGGCUGAAAUCAUAAAACUGCAGACAAUCCAGCAAAAAUCUACAAACUCACCUAGUUCAUUCUUGAAAUACUUCUUGUAUUUGUUAUUUAUGAACCCCUGCCUGCUUCCAAAAAGAACUUGCAGCAUUUUGUAUUAAAAGACGCAUGUGUAUAAUACUUUAAACUUUUAGAGUAAAAUAUCAAGACUCUCAUGUUGGGGAGUGGGGAACGAGGAACAGAACAAUAACGCAUUAAAGUAAAUAACUCUGGAUAAAAGUAA